AGAGGCUGAGCUCCCGGGACCCGGAGCGGAUCGACUGGCGGGCGCCGCGCCGAGGCACCACCGGGCGCCGAGUUCCUGGCGGCUCGCACGGUAAGCGGCGCGGCGCCGCAAAGUAGACUUUGUGGGGUUUCUGACAGCCGGGAGACCCCACCUCGAGCGGGGGCUGCUGGUGCGUUCUCGCGUCGGGCUGCGUCCCCUGGAGCUCCGGCUCUGUGUCCGCGGGAUGCGGGCGCACGGAGGGGCAGGGAGGGAGGCAAGGAGCCGCGCACCACGGUGUCUCCCCAGGCUGCCGCUGCCGGGGCCCUGGGCCGGUCCCUGGGACAGACAGAUCGGCGUGCGGGGGCCGUCUGCCGGGCCCGGGAGCCGGGGGCGCGCAAGACUGUGGAUCCUAAGACUGCCUCCACCCAGCGCCCGGCCCGGGGAAGAGCUUGCGGGAAACCAGGAACCGCAGCGGCCGGACCUCUGCUCUGCGCCGGCUCCUAGGACCUGCCUUAGGUCCCCAGACCCCUCAUGACCUGUUGCCUUGGGUUUGGGAGGUCAGGUUUGUCAUGCCAUUUCCGAUUUCCAGUCAUCCUGGGGGCAGGAUGAAAUUUCAGAGUGGUUUCCUGGCCAAGCUAGAAGCAGAGAAUAGCUAUGGAUACAGCACCUCGUGUAUCUAUCCAGCACUUACUUGGCUUUUUCUGAGUGCCAGGAACUGUGCCAAGCCCUAGCAGCAUGAAGAAUGGCCUUUGGGGAGCUUCUGGGGCUAAGAGGGACAGUAGGAGGAGCAAUUGCAGUGCAGGGUAGUGCGGAAGACUCGAGAUGGAGAAGAGGACGGUGAGGAAGCCAGGAAGGUUUCAGAGAGGAGGUGAGCAUUGACUGGAAGUCGGAGGUUUUGCCAGGCUGAAAAGUGUGUUGGGACUGUGAGUUGAUAGGGAGCAGGAAUUCCAGGUGGGUUUUCUUGUGUAAAGGUAAAGAAACUGAAAAGGUCCGGUGUCCUGACCUAGCACAUCAGAUAAUUCUACAGCAGAUAAUGGAGUAGGACCGGGUCUUGCUGUAGGUAGGAAAUGAGCUCUCGACAUGGCAGGAAGCUAAAACCUGCACAGACCUUAAAGUGCAGCCUUAGAAUAUUUAGAAUUUUAUCCUGGAAUGAAGGAGGGCCGUGGAAGAAUUCUGAUCAGUGAUCAGGUCCCUCUGGCAGCUCUGGGGACAAUGGAUGGAGGCCGGAGCAUCAGAAAGCUGCAGGUAAAUAAAGGCAGCUAAAGCUGACUGCUGGUUGCGCAAAAUCCCCCUGGCUCUUCUGGCUAAAGUCCUACCACUCCCUGUACCUGGCAGCAGCCUGUCUUCUGGGCCUCACCUACACACGUCUGGGUAGGAGCCAGUCAUCUCCAUCCAUCCACAGCCAUGAAUUUCCUCCGGCGACGUCUCUCUGACAGCAGCUUCAUGGCCAACCUGCCUAAUGGCUAUAUGACGGACCUGCAACGCCCAGAUAGCUCCACCAGCUCACCUGCUUCCCCCGCCAUGGAGAGGAGGCACCCCCAGCCCCUGGCUGCCUCCUUCUCCUCUCCAGGAUCCAGCCUUUUUAGCUCCCUCUCCAGUGCCAUGAAGCAGGCCCCUCAGGCCACCUCAGGACUGAUGGAGCCUCCAGGUCCCUCCACGCCCAUUGUUCAAAGACCCAGGAUCCUGUUGGUGAUCGAUGAUGCCCAUACAGACUGGUCGAAGUAUUUCCAUGGGAAGAAGGUGAAUGGAGAGAUUGAGAUCCGAGUGGAGCAGGCUGAAUUCUCAGAGUUGAACCUAGCUGCCUAUGUGACCGGGGGCUGCAUGGUGGACAUGCAGGUCGUGAGAAAUGGGACCAAAGUGGUGAGCAGAUCCUUCAAGCCAGACUUCAUCCUGGUCCGCCAGCAUGCCUACAGCAUGGCCCUGGGGGAAGACUACCGCAGCCUGGUCAUCGGCCUGCAGUAUGGAGGGCUGCCUGCUGUCAACUCUCUCUACUCCGUCUACAACUUCUGCAGCAAGCCCUGGGUGUUCUCUCAGCUCAUUAAGAUCUUCCAUUCCCUGGGUCCUGAGAAGUUCCCGCUUGUGGAGCAAACAUUUUUCCCCAACCAUAAGCCAAUGGUCACAGCCCCACACUUCCCGGUGGUAGUCAAGCUGGGACAUGCCCACGCUGGAAUGGGAAAGAUCAAAGUGGAAAACCAGCUUGACUUCCAGGACAUCACCAGCGUGGUCGCCAUGGCCAAAACCUACGCCACCACCGAGGCCUUCAUCGACUCCAAGUACGACAUCCGCAUCCAGAAAAUUGGAUCCAACUACAAGGCUUACAUGAGAACCUCCAUCUCUGGGAACUGGAAGGCCAACACAGGCUCUGCCAUGCUGGAGCAGGUGGCCAUGACAGAGAGGUACAGGCUGUGGGUGGACAGCUGCUCGGAAAUGUUUGGCGGCCUGGACAUCUGUGCCGUCAAGGCUGUCCACAGCAAGGAUGGCAGAGAUUACAUCAUCGAGGUAAUGGACAGCUCAAUGCCGCUGAUUGGAGAGCAUGUGGAAGAGGACAGACAGCUGAUGGCCGACCUUGUUGUCUCCAAAAUGAGCCAGCUCCCGAUGCCAGGAGGCACAGCGCCCUCCCCCCUCAGACCUUGGGCUCCACAGAUUAAAUCAGCGAAAUCCCCAGGGCAAGCCCAGCUGGGGCCUCAGCUAGGCCAGCCCCAGCCACGCCCACCUCCGCAAGGAGGCCCUCGCCAAGCUCAGUCUCCUCAGCCCCAGAGAUCUGGAAGCCCCUCCCAACAGAGGCUCUCCCCACAAGGCCAGCAGCCCCUGAGCCCCCAGUCCGGAUCUCCACAGCAGCAAAGGUCACCAGGCUCUCCGCAGCUAUCCCGGGCAUCCAGUGGCAGCUCCCCAAACCAGGCCUCCAAGCCAGGUGCCACCCUCGCCUCACAGCCCCGGCCCCCUGUGCAGGGCCGUAGUACCUCCCAGCAGGGUGAAGAGUCCAAGAAGCCAGCACCACCCCAUCCGCAUCUCAACAAAUCUCAGUCCCUGACUAACAGCCUCAGCACAUCCGACACCUCCCAGCGUGGGACCCCAAGUGAAGACGAGGCCAAGGCUGAAACCAUCCGCAACCUGAGGAAGUCUUUUGCCAGCCUGUUCUCUGACUAACGCCAUCCAGGCUGGGAGGGGAAGAGUGCUCUGCUACACUCGUCCCCCUCCUGCCUCAUCUUCCUUCUCAGCCUUGGUUCCUGAUGGGAACAGAAUGGAGGGCCUGAGAACAUACUUUCUAAAUGCCUUUGACCCAGGAACCGAUUAUCUAUAUUUGUUCCCAUUUUCCUUCACCGUGACAUUCCAGCAUUGUCUGACUGUGAGGUGGGCCUUUGAGAGCCUCCAGGUUCCUCAAAACAGGCCUGAGCGAUGGGCAUCACACCCUCUGCCUACCCACGUGCCUGCUUACCUGCCAGAUAACCAAGUGAGAUGUCUGCGAGUGGCUAGUUUUCACAUUCUUACUAGUGUUUGGCUCACCUUUGGGCAAAGGCCCCCUCUAGGCCUUGCCCCACCUCCAUCAAACGCAGACACUGUAGUCAGACCUCAGCAAUAUAGGAGGCAAUAAUCUUUUAACAGUGUUUUGCAAACAAACAAAAAGAGAAAAAUCCCAGCCAGGGGAACUCGCCACCUGCCCACGCUAGUUCCAUCCACGCUCAAGACCCGCCCUUAGACCAGGCAGGCAAAGGCCCCCAUCACACUCGGCCACUAGUGGGGUCCUGAGGCCAAGAAAGAAACCAGACCCUGUAUGACAAGUGGGGUCUUUCAGAACACGACAGAAACAGGGGGGCCCUUGUAAUGCCACUCAUACUCAGAGCAUUAUUCUUAUUUGGACAGCCAAGGGCAGAUCACAGGUUAUUGUAGGAAUAAAGACUAGUUUACAAAGGAGAAAGAGGCCCUGGACUUCCCAAGGAAAGGGUCAGGUUAGGGCUCCUGUACCCAUUCUGUUCCACCACUGUUUGAUCUCUCUGGCCUCCCACCAGGAAUGCCGUUUCCUUUUUAUGGAUCUGUUGGGAACCAGAGAGAAUCAACAGAUCAAUGACAUAGGAUCCGAAGUGCAAUGAUAGUCACUUCUAGUUUGGCAUUUCACAAACUCUGUACAGCAAGGUAUUGGUAGGUUACUCAAUUUCAAAAGGGCCCCAUGGCCAAAUAUGUUUAGGAACCGCUGUUUGUAUUUCUUUUUUUGGAGACGCAUUGUAUAUAAUAUAUGUCAAAGGCUUUCGGAAUUCCUGCAGGAAAGAAAUCAGCUUUGUUAAAUCCAAACUGAUGAUUUGACUCAAUAAGUUAGUUGCAGAGCUGGAAAAAGUAGUCUAACUCCCUUCCCAGUGCUCUUUCCCCUAUACCAGUCUGCCUCUCAUGCUUAGACAGCGUUCAGCGGUGAUCCAAAUCACCAAGCACCUGGUGCUGGAAACAUUGUAGGUGCCAGAAGCAGCCUCCUGGUCCCAAAGAGAGCCCAAGAUAUUAGAACAUAGCCAUGUUAGCCCCUUGCCUCCCACUUCGCAACAUGAGACAUGUCUUCCUUUUGCUGUCCACAGGGAAGGGAGAGAGGGAGGUAAAAAUGGAAGUGGCUUUGGCCUGGAGCAGCUUCUAGUUAUGCCCAAGCAAUGUAGAUUGUUUGGUAAUCAGCCAAGAUCCAUCCAGGUUCCCAGGAGCAUAAAAGCAAUCAUCUCCUUUUUGGUCCUUCAAAACCAAACUGGAGUGGUGACGUCAGGGCCAGAGACCCUCUCCUUCUGUGGGCAUUGGAUCACUUAGAACUCUCAACCUCAGAAAAGCCUGCCUUCAAGCUGGCUUUUGACGGGCUAUUGGCUGGAGACUGGGUCAGUAUUGAAAGUGCUAGCUGUGCACCUGGCUGCCAGAAAGCCACUUGGCCUUUAGGACAGUCCUCUUCACAUUGCCCUCUUCCCUCACUCAUGAUCAGGUCUGGAUUUAAGAGCAAGAGACCCCAGGAUAAUUCAGAAGUCCUCUCUCUCCUCCUGUUCAAGACUCUUGGUCUGGGAUUCAAUAAUAAGUAGCAGACCUGACAUAAGAAAGAUCAGAUAGGUCCAAUUGCCAGUGACUAUUGGGAGCCAUAAUUUGGCAGCUGGAGACUGGUAGGCUCAGGCCUGAUUAACACUGGCUAGGAUCAGCAGCAAAUAAAAUAGCCAUUGUGUGAGGUGAGAGGUGAAGAGGUGAAGGCCUGGUACUCUUUCUAGCGCCCAAAAAGCCCACCACCCUUACUCUGUCUCCAUGCUCGGCUGAGUUCCAUGUUAUAGGACAGUCCCUGCAUGUCUGGCAUGUCUGGAGCUCACUCUGCCCAGUAACACAUCUCCCUUCUUUUUGCUCAGCCUGUGCAAUGCAACAGAACUAGUCUGGCCAGGAGCUGGCAGAAUCCUAUCCAGAGGCAGCUGAGAUGAUGCAGUGGGCAGUCAGACACAUGAAGCUGCUGCUUUGCAGGCAUCAUUGUCGACACAUUCUUCUAGACCCCCAAGGUGGGUGGAGGUGGGGGUCCUGGGGUCAAUAUCCCACAGUCAUGCUUGGGGGAGGUCAGGUGAUGGCAAGGAAUAGAUCAGACCAUUUAUAAUCCGGUAGAACUUUGCUUCAUCCUCCUGCUGCUGCUCACUUAAUUCUUUCACCACUCCCUUGGAAUUUCUGAAGAAAGCCAAGUGGGGCAUAGGGAAAAGAGACGGGAGGUGAAAUUCAAAAUAUCAGAUGUGGGUACCUUUUAAAGUUAUUCUGUUAAAAGAAAUCUAACAGAAGAGAGUAUAAAUAUUGAUUAACAUAAGGUUUGAUGAUUAGCCAGUGAUUCUAGGAGUCCCCUUACACACACACACACACACACACACACACACACGCCUGGACAAUAACUUGGAAUUGACAAAUGCACAUCCUAAAAUCCUGUCACCUCGCUAUGAGUUCAUAGUUCUCUGAUAACCGGCUUCAAGAGGAGAAUGGCUUCCCCACUUGCCCCCAAGAAGAUAGGGAUCACUAGUAUAAGUCACACGAUGAAAGAACCAGAAUACCAGCCUCUCAGACUGGAAGGUUCCUGGGCCCUUCCCCCUUCUUUCCUGACAAGGGCAGGUGAGGUUCCCCCAUUAGAAGGAUCUGGGGCACUGCUUAUAAGAGCAGCCUGUUACAAGAUUCAAGCACAGAGAGCUAUAGGAGUUGAAGUUUGGUUUCUUCCACUUAAAAAAAUAUAUAUCCACCCUCCUUACUCAGGGGUAGACCUUUCAAAUAUUAAUAAAUAAUGCUGUGUGACAUCCUGAAUAAACGGGUAAGAGAAAACUUGUAGGGCAGGGUGUAACCAUGAGGUCCUCAAGUUUCAGGAGAUUAAGAACACAGGAAACCCCUGUGGCAAUCGUCCCUCUUCAACAAUCUCACCCAGUUUUCACUUAGUAAUAAAAGACAGCUCAAAACAUACAACUGAAUGGUAAUAGGCUGGACAAAGUUUCUCAACCUGUGGGCCACGGCCAUGGGCAGAGCUAGUUACAAAGGCAGAUGAAGCUUCAUGUCGGACUAAAGGAGUCCGAAUUUCUGGUCACAGGACCCAGAACCUGCAUCUUUGUCAAUCUCCCCACUUUGAAUGCACUUUGAUGUGAGACCAGCAAACCUGAGCUGGGCUCUGUGGGAAAGCCACUGCAUGAGAAACAGUACUGCUACGGGUGUGCUGCAGUCUCCAACGCAGCUACGAACCCACUCCUUUAGUGAGUGAAACUAGUGGCCCCGUGAACAAUGACCACAUGGCCUAAAUUCUCCCAUAUUCCUAUAUUCUGUCCUUUGGCCUCAGACACACCUCAGCAUCCAAAGGAUAUCUCCCAGAUACUCCAGUAUCUGUGUACAACAGCCGCAGAACCUCCUUCCAAGCUCCAAAUCAGGCCAGGCAUCCUGAUUUUUAUAACCAUACUCAUAUAUCCAGAUCCAUGACAUAACACUAGUUUAUAGCCAACACAUUUAAAUAAUUUCCCCACUGGGGCCAGGCGCAGUGGCUCACAUCAGUAAUCCCAGCACUUUGGGAGGCCGAGGUGGGCGGAUGACUAGGUCAGGAGAUCGAGACCAUCCUGGCUAACACGGUGAAACCCCAUCUCUACUAAAAAUAUAAAAAAUUAGCCGGGCGUGGUAGCGGGCGCCUGUAGUCCCAGCUACUAGGGAGGCUGAGGCAGGAGAAUGGCGUGAACCCGGGAGGCGGAGCUUGCAGUGAGCCGAGAUCGCACCACUGCACUCCAGCCUGGGCAACAGAGUGAGACUCUGUCUCAAAAUAAUAAUAAUAAUAAUAAUAAUACUUUCCCCAUUGGUCUGUGUAUGAACAUAGGAACCAAGGACACAUAGGUCUCAUGGCGACCCUAAAAUAGUCUGUUCUGUCACAUAGACUAGUACCUGUUCCUUCCAAACAUGUAACCUUUAAUAAUUGUGACAUUUUGAAAUGGGAAAGGGCAAAAAGGAGGGAGAGGGGAGUCAUGCUGUAUAGACUCUAAAAUGUUAUGUUUGUUGUUUUUCUUGCUUUGUUUCACAACUUUGAGCCAGAGAGAGGCUAGCAUUUUCCCUCCAAGCUGACUCGGGGAAGCUGAAACACAACAAAGACCUAUUUGAUUUGUUCACAAUGAACAGGGAUUUAAAAACGCAGCCUUAGCGGACAGCUCUACCAGCCACAGAAAAGUUCUUCCAGAUCUUCCUCCCGUCAGCGCGAUAAAAUGGUACCGUACUUUGGUUAAAUGUAAAAUCAGCUUUCCAGGAACAGUGGCAUAUCCUUUCUCUUCCAUCAGUUCCCUAGAUUCUCUUCAUUACUACAUUCUCUAGCCUAACAUUCCGUCCCUGCUGAAUUAACUAAUAUUCAGAUACAUUCAAGAUAGAACUAACACUCAAUUCUAUCUUUCCAAAAUUUAAGGGGAUGAUAGGUCUUCACUCACAUGGUAACAAACACAGCAGCAAACCCCAUAAAACUGAACAUCAACUGCCUUCUGGAAGUUCUCAUCUGGCAAGCUAGUGCAGGUAUCUUGUGCAUGGGUCAAGAGAGUGAAGCUCAGAGCACAUUGCUUGGCACCCAGCAGGUGUUCAGGACAUGUUUUAGCUCAGCCCUCCUAGAAAACUAUGAAAUAAAAUCCAAACAAAAGUAUUAAGAUUGAAGUAAAAAGAUGUUUUUCUAAGAGUAUCAAUAUAUGGAAGUCACUUGCCCAGGAACAGAAUCAAACAAACCAAAACCCAGUAAAAUGAGAUAGAGAAAAGAAGCGGAAGAAGAUCAAUGGCAGGUUUUCAACCUCAAAAAGACCUCUUCCAAACUGAAUCUGAAGAGGAAUGGGAGGAGGCAGAAUGAGAACAUGAGACCUCUCCUUGGGGCCCCUUUCAUGCGCGUCUGUGUGAAGAGACCACUAAACAGGCUUUGUGUGAGCAACAUGGCUGUUUAUUUCACCUGGGUGCAGGCCGGAUGAGUCCGAAAAGAGAGUCAGCAAAGGGAGUAGGGAUGGGGCCGUUUUAUAGGAUUUGGGAAGGUAAUGGAAAAUUACAUGCAAAGGGGGUUGUUCUCUGGUGGGCAGGGGCGGGGGUCACAAGGUGCUCAGUGCGGGAGCUUCUGAGCCAGAAGAAGGAAAUUUACAGGGUUAAUCACUCAGUUAAGGUGGGGCAGGAACAAAUCACAAUGGUGGAAUGUCAUCAGUUAAGGCGGGGCAGGGCCUUUUCACUUCUUUUGUGAUUCUUCAGUUACUUCAGGCCAUCUGGGCGUAUACGCGCAAGUCACAGGGGAUGCGAUGGCUUGGCUUGGGCUCAGAGGCCUGACAUUCCUGCCUUCUUAUAUUAAUAAGAAAAAUAAAACAAAAUAGUGUUGAAGUGUUGGGGCGACGAAAAUUUUUGGGGGGUGGUAUGGAGAGAGAAUGGGCGAUGUUUCUCAGGGCUGCUUCGAGUGGGAUUAGGGGCGGCGUGGGAACCUAGAGUGGGAGAGAUUAAGCUGAAGGGAGGUCUCGUGGUAAGGGGUGAUAUUGUGGGGAUGUUAGAAGAAACAUUUGUUGUGUAGAAUGAUUGGUGACGGCCU